ACACAACUUUUUUUCCUUAGUCUGUAUACUUUCUGCUGUCACUAGCAUAACAGAAAAGACGAAUGGCUUUUGUUUUAAACUGAGGGCACUUUUACAAAAGUCAUCUUUCCAUUUAUUUUUCUUUCAGAAAAAAGAAUUUGGGUUUUGAGCUUUUUUAAAAAAAAAAGACAAACACUUUCCUUGACUUUGAGAAAUAAUUUAAGUCAAAGAAUCUGCUCUAUGCUAACCAAGAGAUAGAGCACAGCAAAGAUCUGCCAGCCCCAGGCCUCUACCUAGUGGCCUGGAAAUUCAAGUAUUCUUAUUGGUGGAGGCCAUUUGUUUCUGAUUAGAAGCUGUCUAAACCUCCUACUCCUCAACUCAAAGGAAAACACAGAGCAUACCAUGGCCAAGAAAGUUGCAGUGAUUGGAGCUGGUGUGAGUGGCCUCUCCUCCAUCAAAUGCUGUGUGGAUGAGGACCUGGAGCCCACCUGCUUUGAGAGAAGUGAUGACAUUGGGGGAUUAUGGAAGUUUACUGAAUCUUCCAAAGAUGGGAUGACCAGGGUCUAUAAGUCAUUAGUGACAAAUGUCUGUAAGGAAAUGUCAUGUUACAGUGACUUCCCUUUCCACGAAGAUUAUCCUAAUUUCAUGAACCAUGAAAAAUUUUGGGACUAUCUCCAAGAAUUUGCUGAGCACUUUGACCUCCUGAAAUACAUUCAGUUUAAGACCACUGUGUGCAGCAUAACGAAGCGUCCAGACUUCUCCGAAACUGGUCAGUGGGAUGUUGUCACAGAGACAGAGGGCAAGCAAAAUAGAGCUGUCUUUGAUGCUGUUAUGGUUUGCACUGGACAUUUCCUGAAUCCCCAUUUACCUUUGGAAGCCUUUCCUGGAAUUCAUAAGUUUAAAGGUCAGAUCCUGCAUAGUCAAGAGUACAAGAUCCCAGAAGGCUUUCAGGGCAAACGCGUCUUGGUGAUUGGUCUUGGGAACACUGGAGGAGACAUUGCUGUGGAACUCAGUCGAACGGCAGCUCAGGUACUUCUCAGUACUAGAACUGGUACCUGGGUUCUUGGGCGCUCUUCAGAUUGGGGCUAUCCUUAUAAUAUGAUGGUUACAAGAAGAUGCUGUAGUUUUAUUGCACAAGUUCUGCCUUCACGUUUUCUAAACUGGAUUCAAGAAAGGAAGUUGAAUAAGAGAUUUAAUCAUGAGGAUUAUGGAUUAAGUAUUACCAAAGGGAAAAAAGCAAAAUUCAUUGUGAAUGAUGAGCUGCCAAACUGUAUCCUCUGUGGGGCAAUCACUAUGAAAACCAGCGUGAUUGAAUUUACAGAAACCUCUGCUGUCUUUGAAGAUGGGACAGUGGAAGAAAACAUUGAUGUUGUGAUCUUCACUACAGGAUAUACAUUUUCUUUUCCAUUUUUUGAAGAACCUCUUAAAAGCCUCUGUACAAAGAAGAUAUUUCUAUACAAGCAAGUCUUUCCCUUAAACCUAGAGAGAGCGACAUUAGCCAUCAUCGGCCUUAUCGGCCUUAAAGGAUCCAUCUUAUCAGGCACAGAGCUCCAAGCACGAUGGGUCACAAGAGUAUUCAAAGGACUCUGUAAGAUACCUCCAUCCCAAAAAUUGAUGAUGGAGGCUACUGAAAAGGAACAGCUCAUUAAAAGCUGUUCUAUUUGGACUGAUCAGACGUUGUUCUCACAUCAAAUCCAAGAACUGAAAACAUUAUUUAAAGUUUCUCUCGAGUUUUUAAGAACCUACAACUAUUUAUGGAGAAAAAGCAGCCCAAGGAUGAUCUUUUUGAUAGACUCAAUACUGGUAUUCUGAAUAAGCAUCUCCAGGAUCUCAUGGAGAGCUUGACAGCCAAGGUAUUCCAUACAUACAAUGCCUCCAUCACGCUACAGCAGCAGCUAGAAGAACUCACAGCCCCGGAUGAGAACAUCCCAGCGAAGAUCCUUUCUUAUAACCGUGCCAAUCGAGCUGUUGCAAUUCUUUGUAACCAUCAGAGGGCACCACCAAAAACUUUUGAGAAGUCUAUGAUGAACUUGCAAACUAAGAUUGAUGCCAAGAAGGAACAGCUAGCAGAUGCCCGGAGAAACCUGAAAAGUGCUAAGGCUGAUGCCAAGGUCAUGAAAGAUGCAAAGAUGAAGAAGGUAGUAGAGUCAAAGAAGAAGGCUGUUCAGAGACUGGAGGAACAGUUGAUGAAGCUGGAAGUUCAAGCCACAGACCGAGAGGAAAAUAAACAGAUGGCCUUGGGAACCUCCAAACUCAAUUAUCUGGAUGCUAGGAUCACUGUGCCUUGGUGCAAGAAGUGGGGUGUCCCAAUUGAGAAGAUUUACAACAAAACCCAGCGAGAAAAGUUUGCCUGGGCCAUUGAAAUCGCUGAUGAAGACUACGAGUUUUAGCCAGUCUCAAGAGGCAGGGUUCUGUGAAAAGGAACAGUGUGGUUUGGGAAAGAUGGAUAAACUGAGCCUCGCUUGCCCUCGUGCCUGGGUGAGAGAGGCAGCAAGUCUUAACAAACCAACAUCUUUGCAAAAAGCUAAACCUGGAGAUAUUAUAAGGGACAGCUGAGCCAGUUGUCCUACGGACAACUUAUUUAAAAAUAUUUCAGCUAUCAAAAUUCUAGCUGUAUGAUUUGUUUUGAAUUUUGUUUUUAUUUUCCAGAGGGCAAGUGGAUGGGAAUUUGUCAGCGUUCUACCAGGCAAAUUCACUGUUUCACUGAAAUGUUUGGAUUCUCUUAGCUACUGUAUGCAAAGUCCGAUUAUGUUGGUGUGUUUUUACAGUUAGGGUUUUGCAAUAACUUCUAUAUUUUAAUAGAAAUAAAUUCCUAAACUCCCUCCCCUCUCCCCCAUUUCAGGAAUUUAAAAUUAAGUAGAACAAAAAACCCAGUGCGCCUGUUAGAGUCGUCACUGUCUAUUGUCAUAGGGAUCAAUUUUCAUUAAACUUGAAGCAGUC